AAGGAAUCGAAACUCGGCGGCCUUGGGGGCGGCCCUACGUAGCCUGGCUUCUGGGUGAGUGACUCGCCAGGGACGGGUGGAGGAUAGGGAUGCGGGCAAUGCCGCGGCCAACCUCCGUAGCUGUUGCCGGUCCAAAAAGACACGUCAUUUUUUUCUCACUCCCUCCCGCGCCCCCUCCUUUGACUAGGGAGCGGCCCACUCCUGGGCAUCCCUUUCCCCAGUCACCCCCACACCCAGCUGUCCACACCCUUUCCCCUGUCACCCUCACCCCCAGCUGUCCAGGCCCUUCUUGGUCAUUCACUUCUCUAAUUACUCCUUUUCUUUUCGUACUCUUACUGGGGCGCCUUCAGUUUUUUUUCAUUCAUUGAGACUGCUAAAUGCUUCUUUCCGAUACAAAUUAUCGGAAAGAAAAGAGGGACAUUGGCUAGGACGGUACUCCCUGGGGCAUCUGAGUGGUGAAUAUCGACCCCCUGCACUUGAUCGAGGGCUAACAGGUAUUCGUCGUUUCUCCAAUGUCUAACCUGUAUACGGUAUUCAUUCCAGCCUUCGGCUGUUUGUUGAGUAACUACUACUACGUGCAAGGUAGGCUGACACCCUCUACACAAAAGAAACCCCAAUACUCGAAAGCGAGAUAAAAUACCCACGAAAACUCUAGUACAAAUCAAACCAUCAGUUGCUCCAAGAGGUGAUGGAAAUUUGCUAAGGUGAUCAAAGACAGACGUACCAGAAUUAAAAUUGACCCUUGCGCCUUAUGUGUAGAAGACAUUUUGGUUUUUAGAUUGGAAUUUCAAAUUGGAUUGAGCAAGAUCUCAAGGCAGAAUUUCAUUUCUCUAAAAACGCCAUAUCUCAUUGCCCAAUCUUGUGAUCAUUUCAUCAUCUGUAAAUUGAGAACAGUGCAUCCUUUACAGGAUAUUUCCAAAUUUUAAUGUGAUAUUGUUUGUAAGCCAGACAUCUUACGCAAGUAGAAGGUUUUAAUAUUAAAGAGACAGCAUAACAUAAUGGGAAAUGACACUGGAUUAGGUCAGAACACCAGUAUCUGAAUGCUGAUUUUUCCAUUUACUUGACAAUGGUUGUCAUGGAUGCACUGGUAGAAGAUGAUAUCUGUAUUCUGAAUCAUGAAAAAGCCCAUAAGAGAGAUACAGUGACUCCAGUUUCAAUAUAUUCAGGAGAUGAAUCUGUUGCUUCCCAUUUUGCUCUUGUCACUGCAUAUGAAGACAUCAAAAAACGACUUAAGGAUUCAGAGAAAGAGAACUCUUUGUUAAAGAAGAGAAUAAGAUUUUUGGAAGAAAAGCUAAUAGCUCGAUUUGAAGAAGAAACAAGUUCCGUGGGACGAGAACAAGUAAAUAAGGCCUAUCAUGCAUAUCGAGAGGUUUGCAUUGAUAGAGAUAAUUUGAAGAGCAAACUGGACAAAAUGAAUAAAGACAACUCUGAAUCUUUGAAAGUAUUGAAUGAGCAGCUACAAUCUAAAGAAGUAGAACUCCUCCAGCUGAGGACAGAGGUGGAAACUCAGCAGGUGAUGAGGAAUUUAAAUCCACCUUCAUCAAACUGGGAGGUGGAAAAGUUGAGCUGUGACCUGAAGAUCCAUGGUUUGGAACAAGAGCUGGAACUGAUGAGGAAAGAAUGUAGCGAUCUCAAAAUAGAACUACAGAAAGCCAAACAAACGGAUCCAUAUCAGGAAGACAAUCUGAAGAGCAGAGAUCUCCAAAAACUAAGCAUUUCAAGUGAUAAUAUGCAGCAUGCAUACUGGGAACUGAAGAGAGAAAUGUCUAAUUUACAUCUGGUGACUCAAGUACAAGCUGAACUACUAAGAAAACUGAAAACCUCAACUGCAAUCAAGAAAGCCUGUGCCCCUGUAGGAUGCAGUGAAGACCUUGGAAGAGACAGCACAAAACUGCACUUGAUGAAUUUUACUGCAACAUACACAAGACAUCCCCCUCUCUUACCAAAUGGCAAAGCUCUUUGUCAUACCACAUCUUCCCCUUUACCAGGAGAUGUAAAGGUUUUAUCAGAGAAAGCAAUCCUCCAAUCAUGGACAGACAAUGAGAGAUCCAUUCCUAAUGAUGGUACAUGCUUUCAGGAACACAGUUCUUAUGGCAGAAAUUCUCUGGAAGACAAUUCCUGGGUAUUUCCAAGUCCUCCUAAAUCAAGUGAGACAGCAUUUGGGGAAACUAAAACUAAAACUUUGCCUUUACCCAACCUUCCACCACUGCAUUACUUGGAUCAACAUAAUCAGAACUGCCUUUAUAAGAAUUAAUUUGGAAGAGAUUCACGAUUUCACCAUGAGGACACUUAUCUCUUUCAGUGGUCCUCCCAAGAAAUUAUUUAACAAACUGAAAGGAGAUUUUGAUUAAAAUUUUGCAGAGGUCUUCAGUAUCUAUAUUUGAACACACUGUACAAUAGUACAAAAACCAACAUAGUUGGUUUUCUAGUAUGAAAGAGCACCCUCUAGCUCCAUAUUCUAAGAAUCUGAAAUAUGCUACUAUACUAAUUAAUAAGUAAACUUAAGGUGUUUAAAAAACUCUGCCUUCUAUAUUAAUUGUAAAAUUUUGCCUCUCAGAAGAAUGGAAUUGGAGAUUGUAGACGUGGUUUUACAAAAUGUGAAAUGUCUAAAUAUCUGUUCAUAAAAAUAAAAGGAAAACAUGUUUCUUCAAAUUGCAUAAUGGAACAAAUGGCAAUGUGAGUAGGUUACAUUUCUGUUGUUAUAAUGCGUAAAGAUAUUGAAAAUAUAAUGAAAUAAAAGCAUCUUAGGUUAUACCAUCUUUAUAUGCUAUUGCGUUUCAAUAUUUAAGAUUUAAAGUGAUUUUUUGGUCACAGUGUUUUGUUGAUAAAAUUUUUUUAGAAUUGAAGUUUGAAUUCUAAGACUUGAAACAACCUGAUCACUGAAGCCAACUUUGUCCCAGCACAUUCCUUAAGUCCUAAUUGGGAAAAAAAAAAAAAAAAAUGAAAUAGUUGAAAAACUCUGGGGUGUAAACAAAUGAUUGUAACCCUACACACUAUUCAAUAAGUAGUAGAAGGAGCAUCACACAGAUUUCAGUCUAAUCUGCCCUUCUGUGGGCCAUAAUAUAAACAUAAAUGUGUGUAAUGAUAAAAAGUCAUUUUCUUCAAAGAGACUACAGCUAGCUGCACAUUGUGUAGAGCAGCUUCUAAAUUGUUAGACUUUGUGUUGAAAUGUAAUAUUCUAUUUAUUGAGAAAGUGAUUUAAAAUUAUUAUUUUUAAUCAUAGAAAUCAGGGUUUGGGCUGUAUUGAUAUUGUCGAUCAUGAAAUGUCCACACUUAUUCUAAGUGGCCAAUUAUUUGGAAAUAAAGAAGGAAAUAAAGAUGGCUUCACAUGGAAAUUUAAGUUCUUUCAGGGUGGAGAUUUACUUGGUUCAUACACCUUUUGCCUGAAUUAAAGUAUUUCAUGUAGGAGGACUUUUAUCCUUUUUGAUAGACAGUUUCAUAUAUCUUGAACUCAAUAUCUCAGAUCUCUUCUACUGUAUUACUGAAUAGCAUACAUACAUAGACAAUGUUCGCCAUUCACUAGAUAUUUUUUUCUAUUAUCUUACACUUAUUCAAGCUUGUCUGUGAUUAAUGGAAUUGGUGUCAGAUGCUGGAAUUUAUUCUGACCAAUGAACACAGCUGACUCAGGGGAGUACAAUCUCCUGCCAAGUAAUAGAACCAAACCCAAUAUGCAUAAAAGAAAUACAAUACUCCAGGCUUUAGCUGAAGGAAGCAACUACCUGUGUAAUAACAAAGCAGCAAAAACUAUUUCUCAUGUGGCUGCAUAGGCUGUAUAUUAUAUCUGAUCUCUAAUGUAGCUUACUGGUUUGCCUUUUUUAAAACCAAAAUUGGAAAUUUUCCUUUGUAAAGAAAAAAAGUCUUAUGAGAUAAUUGCUUGAUUAAUGUUUUGAACAAUACCAAGAAAUUGUUUAAUUAAAAUAAAUAUUUUUGUUUGAAAUUGAAGUGGAUGUGAAAUAUUGUCCUUGCCUAUAGAUCUCAAAAUCUAGUACUAAUUGUUGGUUGUUAAUAUGAUUCAUACAAUAGACAUUUGUUAAACCAGCUUUUGAGUGGAGAAAAUUAUUUUCCAUUUAAACAGUACAGUGAUGAUAGCUAUCAAACAGGUAUACUAAAAAGUCAGUGACUGUGACAGUUUAAAGUGUUAGACAAAUGAUGUAUAAGGUUCUUUAGUAAGGAAAGAUUAGCCAAAAAUUUUUUACCCAGCUAGAAGCUUUUAAAUCUACACUUGAUAUCUCUGUUCUAGGUAAAAUUCAAACAACCAAAAAACAGUGGCCCAUCUGUAGCUUAUGAAUCUAUUUAAAAUUGAAUAUUUUAUGUUGACUUCUUUCAUACUAGCUGAAACUUGCUCUAAAGAGCUUCCUUUGGAAUCUUUAGAUUUCUUUUUAUAAGGUUCAAUUCAGUACAUCCAUAAAUCGACAGAAUGAAGAAAACAUAACAAAAAGCCACCUAUUCCUUCCUCUUGCUCCCUUAUUAGCUAAAGUAAAAUUUACAUCUGUAAGACUUACUGAGUUGCUGCCAAAAUGGAACUGAAUUCUUAAAAGCAGGAACAUGCCUAUGUGAAACAUUAGAAAACCAAAAUAAAUGGGAAAAUUCAGACUUGAAGAGCUGAAUCAUGUGACAACAAAGUACUGAUCUUAAUUCAGAAAGGCUACUUGGAGAAGGUGUAUCUUAAGGGGUAAAAAACCUGUGGGUUACCACAUAUUAACAGGGAAUAAUAUCAACAGAGGCACCCAUAAGCAAGCAAGACACAACUGAGACAGAUGUACCAGGUGAAAAAAAUCUUCAGUAUGGAUACACAUGGGUAUUCUGAAGGCUACAAUGAAUGGUUUAGUCUUUGACAUAAGGAGGAUGAACAUAUUAUUUAUACUGUGUAAUCUAAUCUGGCUUCUAUGGGGAAAGCAACAUGUACAUAAGUGAAUUUUCUACAUGAAGUGGGCUACUUCUGAUUUUAAUCAAAGCUAUAAAAUAGAUUGUAUAUUUCACUAGCUUCUUAAAGUAACUCUUCCAUUUUCAUUUAUCUCUAAAAACAGUUAACUUCCUGUGCUCUAGGAAAUGCACCAAUACCAAAGGUCAAUGUGGAAAUAUGGGCAUGUUUGCCCCUAUGCUGUGUGGUCUCUAGAUUUCUAUAUUUGCUUUGCUUUUGUCUGCUCUAGUAAUCUCCCUCCUUUUGAUCUGUGGCCUGGGAAAAUGUGGUUUCUUUGUAUUUCAAAUAAAAGUAAAAUAGUUUUUUGAGUGGUUCACUCAAGAGUAAA